AAGUACCUCUAUGGGCCGGGUCAGACUCGGUGUUUGCGGAUUACCUUAAUAGGGCAAGCCCCCCACUCCUUAACGCAAACAGCUUCUGCCCUCUGUCCUCUGAAUCAUAGCCACUCCCAUCUUAGGCUUUUUUUGGGGAGGGGCGGGGGGCUGGUGCGGAAUCGGAAUAACAAGCUCCGUGGGGGUGCGCAAGAAGCAUCGCCGUGUCUUCGGACCCAGACUAUGAACUGAUCUAUGACGCUGAACUUGAGUUUGAGUUUGCCUUGGAAGCCAUGUGGCAAGAUUCUGGGAAAGUUCUUCCUUGCUCCGCAGAAGAGAGAUGCCACUGGAGUCAUCCUCUUCAAUGCCACUAUCCUUCCCAUCUCUCUUACCCUCAGUACCACACAAUACUAACCCUUCCCCUCCUCUGAUGUCUUACAUCACCUCCCAGGAGAUGAAGUGUAUUCUUCACUGGUUUGCCAAUUGGUCAGGUCCCCAGCGUGAACGUUUCCUAGAGGACCUGGUAGCUAAGGCAGUGCCAGAAAAAUUACAACCACUGCUGGAUAGUCUGGAGCAGCUUAGUGUGUCUGGGGCAGACCGACCACCUUCUAUCUUUGAGUGCCAGCUACAUCUUUGGGAUCAGUGGUUUCGAGGCUGGGCUGAGCAGGAGCGCAAUGAAUUUGUCAGACAGCUGGAGUUCAGUGAGCCAGACUUCGUGGCAAAGUUUUACCAAGCAGUGGCUGCUACAGCUGGUAAGGACUGAUAGGCAUUCAGACCAAAGAAGAUAACCAUAGCUGAUGGAGCCAUGACUCUCUACAAUGAUAACUCAAUUCAAAUGUGUCGCCUAAAGCUCUGGAACUGGUAUUCCAACCAGCUGACCGAACUCACUGACCAGUACAGGCAUGGUUAUUUCAACAUUAAUAGCAUGUCAACUGGACUCCUAUUUGUAAAUGUUAUCAAUCUAAGCAAUCCAGCUCAUCAGUCUACUAGUUUGCUUCUUUCCGAGAGAUGUCAAGUCCUCAAGAAUUUGAUGGCUUCUUCUGCAGCUAUAACCACAAGGAACCUACACAUUGUAACUCAAGUCCACUGCUGGCUCAUGAAAUGUGUAAAGUAGAACCCUCCUUCCCGAGAAAUAAGACAGGACAAUAAAAGGUGGCGUUUUUGUACUUUACCUGGAUUCCAUUGGCUGGUUUUACCACUCCUAUCAGAUUGUAGUGUAAUUGUGUGAUACGCAAACCAUUAGUUUUCCCAGUGAUGAUUUAAUAAAAUUAUGAAAAAUCAGGAGAGGGAGAUAAUUAGUUGCUUCCUCCUUCACACUGUUUGAAUCGAACUCGCGGUGACUUUUUUUUUUUUUUAAAAACAUGGGUUGUCACUUAAGUUUGGAGUGCAGUGGCAUGAUCAUCAGUGAGCGUGAGAUCACUGUAACCUCAAAUUCUAGGCUGAAGUAAUCUUUCUGCCUCAGUCUCCUGAGUAUCUAGGACUACAGGCCCGCACAACAAUAUCUGGCUAAUUUUUAAAUUAUUCUGUAGAUACAGGGGUCAUGCUACGUUUUCUAGUCUGGUCUUGAACUGCUGGCCUCAAGCGAUCCAUUCUCACCUUGGCCUCCCAAAGUGCUGGGAUUACAGGCAUGAACCAUCAUACCUGGCCUUUUUCUAAGGCAUAUGUAUGUGAUAUUCUUGGAACUGGUAGCAGGUGUUCCUAUUCUGUAAGUUUGCUUUACAACAAUACGAAAAUAAGUGACAAUUUACAGGUUGAACAAUUUAUUUUUGUACCAAAAUAAAGAAUGGAUCUUUAGAACUGUAAAACUUCACCCUUUUUUCAUUGCCAGGCUAUAUAAUAUUGACAACCGGGGAAAGAGGCAUUCCAAAGAAAGUAGAAAUUAAGUAUACACAAUAGAUUUUCCAUCCAGUUGUCUCACAAGAAAUUAUUCUCUUCCUUACCCCCUGUCAUGUUCUGGGCAACAUCACACCUCCCUUAUUCCUCUAACUGGGACCCUUGUGCUGUGGAGCUCUGGUGAAUGGUAAGAGGCAGAUGGUCUCACAGGAAGAGUGGCUCUUUUCUGGUAGGCUGUGGUUCCCAUUACACCCACCAGGAUUAGCAGCAUUAGGCAGAGUCCCAUGGACAGCCUUAGGUGGGUCAUGGAGGGAUUAUGGUCUGAAGUAACCAGCAACCUAGGAACAUAGAAGGUAAUAUUUGGCAUGGAAUAAUGCCUAGCCUUAGUAGAUAAAGCGGCAUUACCUUUUUUUUUUUUUUUUUUUGGAGACAAGGUCUUGGUCUGUUGCCCAGGCUGGAGUGCAGUGGUGUGAUCUUGGCUCACCGUAAUCUCCGCCUCCCAGGCUCAAGCAAUUCUCCUGCCUCAACCUUCCGAAUAGCUGGGACUACAGGCGCACGCCGCACCACCACGUCUGGCUAAGGGGCUUUACCCUUAAAGAUAGAGCUCAUGAAGCCCCGCCUCAUCCAAGCAUUAAGCUAAACAGGAAAUCAUUAAGAGGGACUAUCGAACCUUAAAGUAGAAAUAAGAUCAAGAUCUAAGUCUUCUAGCAUCUUAUAUUAUUGGAAGAAGACCUAACUUGGCAGCAAGGGAAGUGGCUUAAGGGAAGAGUCAGUCUAUGUUCUUUAGGUAGCUAGACACAAUCCCUAACAGUGCUUAAGAAAGGAAGGGGGCUGGGAGUGGUGGCAGUGGCUCCCAGCACUUUGGGAGGCAGAGGCCGGUGGGUUGCUUUAGCUCAGGAGUUGGAGACAAGCCUGGGCAACAUGGUGAAACUGUCUCUAUCAAAAAUACAAAAAUUAGCUGGCAUGGUGGUGUGCACCUGUAGUCCCAGCUACUUGGGAAGCUGAGGUGGGGGAAUCACUUGAGCCUAGGGAGGUCGAGGCCACAGUGAGCUGAGAUCACCCCACUGCAUUCCAGCCUGGGUGACAGAGCGAGACCCUGUCUCAAAAAAGAAGAAGAAAAAGGUGGGGGGAGGGGACUAAGAUCCCUAUGUCCUAGAGAUGGGGGAAUGUGUUAUUGUAUGGGAGGAGGGAGUCAGGUAGUGACGGGACUGGAUGAUCGUGUUAGGGAUCUUUGUUCUCUGAAACGCAACCCUGUCUAGGACAAUAUACACGUGAGUGAGUGCUUAAUAAAUUUAAUUUCAAACA